AUAGAUGAGAAUGCUGAGGCCUCAGGAGGGCAAGGGACUCGCCCACGGUCACGGAACCCUAAGUCAGGGGUGGAGAAGGACCCCCUGACGCCAGCCCACCUCCCCUGCCCCUCAGCAGGCCUGGCUCCAGCACAGAGAAGAGCCAUUGUUGCUGCUCUGGGGGCCCUAGGAGCCUGGGAUGUAUCCUGCCUUUGUUUCUAGAGCCUUUGUUUGUUGUAUUUCCUCUGUCUCCAGACAUCGCAGGCCGGUGGGACCCGGCGCCUGUGCACGCUCACGUAGCGGGGCCUGUUCGGGUCCCUCGUGGGUCCCUUCAGUUCGAGCUCUGUCCUUGCCUCAGCGGCCCGUCACCCAUAGGGUGGCAGAGAUGGGCCGGGGGAGGGAGUGGGCAGCAGUGCGGACCGAGUCCUGGCGCAUGGGGUUUCCCUGGUGCUGGAGCCGGGCGUUUCGGGGGUGUGGGCGGGGCUGGGGUCAUAUCCCCUGCAUGCCCCGCAUGCCAUGGCUGUACUCACAUGGCAAGAGGUGGUGAUCGCCAGCUCAGGGAAGGUGGGGGUUCCUUCAUCCUGUGGAGAGGGGGCUGAAUUGGGGUCCCCUGAGCUGUAGGGUGCAGUGCCUGACAGGCCGUGGGGAGGGCCGAGGGGAUGGGGACUGACAGGCCCCGGGCCCAUGCCGCCCCCUGGCACGGGUGGAUGCCCCGCCUCCCGGGGGUGCCCAGCUGGACUGUGGCACCCCCAAAGGACCCCACAUGUCACUGUUCCCCCGCAGGGCUUCCCACGGCACGACAUGGAGACCUGUGGUUGCGAGGCUCCCUGGGGCUCGGCUUGGACCGCGAUGGGGCUGGGCCCUGGCCUCCUAACGGGGCUGCUGUCUGGGGCGGUAGCUGGGGGGGCGCUCUCCCCCCUGCCCGCGACUCGGAGCACCCCCACCCCUCCCCUGCCGGGCCAGGCCGGGCGGCGUUGUUGGCGGGGGCCCCGGUGGAGGCCCGGCCUGGGCGGCGCCCGCCAUGAAUGGGCUGUCGCUGAGUGAGCUCUGCUGCCUCUUCUGCUGCCCGCCCUGCCCCGGCCGCAUCGCUGCCAAGCUCGCCUUCCUGCCGCCGGAGGCCACCUACUCCCUGGUGCCUGAGCCCGAGCCGGGGCCUGGUGGGGCCGGGGCCGCCCCCUUGGGGACCCUGAGAGCCUCCUCGGGCGCACCCGGGCGCUGGAAGCUGCACCUGACGGAGCGUGCCGACUUCCAGUACAGCCAGCGCGAGCUGGACACCAUCGAGGUCUUCCCCACCAAGAGCGCCCGCGGCAACCGCGUCUCCUGCAUGUAUGUUCGCUGCGUGCCUGGUGCCAGACAAGGACACCAGGCUCAGGGAGGCCAUCCCCAGCUGGCAUGGGUGGGCAGGCUGGGCGACUCCAACAACCCAGCGCCUGGUGGUUGCCUGCUGGGCAAGAGCUGGGGCACAGGGGCUGCCCUGGCCUGCGGGUACAUCCACCUUCUCGCCAGGUACACGGUCCUCUUCUCGCACGGCAAUGCCGUGGACCUGGGCCAGAUGAGCAGCUUCUACAUUGGCCUGGGCUCCCGCCUCCACUGCAACAUCUUCUCCUACGACUACUCCGGCUACGGUGCCAGCUCGGGCAGGCCUUCCGAGAGGAACCUCUAUGCCGACAUCGACGCCGCCUGGCAGGCCCUGCGCACCAGGUACGGCAUCAGCCCGGACAGCAUCAUCCUGUACGGGCAGAGCAUCGGCACGGUGCCCACCGUGGACCUGGCCUCGCGCUACGAGUGUGCCGCGGUGGUGCUGCACUCGCCGCUCACCUCGGGCAUGCGCGUCGCCUUCCCCGACACCAAGAAGACCUACUGCUUCGACGCCUUCCCUAACAUCGAGAAGGUGUCCAAGAUCACGUCUCCCGUGCUCAUCAUCCACGGCACGGAGGACGAGGUGAUCGACUUCUCGCACGGGCUGGCGCUCUACGAGCGCUGCCCCAAGGCGGUGGAGCCGCUGUGGGUGGAGGGCGCCGGGCACAACGACAUCGAGCUCUACAGCCAGUACCUGGAGCGCCUGCGUCGCUUCAUCUCCCAGGAGCUGCCCAGCCAGCGCGCCUAGCGGCGGCCCCAACCGGCCGGACCUCAGCAAUAAGGCGGCCCCCGGACCUCACCCCGCGCCGGCCCCCACCCAGGGGCUGCAUGUGGACCCCCCGGGCGGCCCAGGGGACCCCGCCCCGACCCAGGGGCUGUGGACGAUGUACAGGCAACAGAGCUACGCACUCCUUUCCUUUUGGAAGCAAGAAGAAAAUACGUGAAAACGGAAAUUAAAGAUUUAAAAUUUUAGGGCUGCUCUCCUUCCUUUCAUGGCUCUGCUCACUCUCUCGAGCGCUCAGCGAGCUCGAAAGGGGGCCGGGGUUCCCAGGUUUCGUCCCUGAGUCCCUAGGAGAGAUCGGCACGGACCCCCUUAUAGGUUUUACUCUGCGGAAGUGGGGUGGGUCUCUGUCUAGUC